GCAAAGGCCUGAGAAUCACAAGCGCGCGGCCGCUCCCAUUUCUUCGCGAUUCCAGAACCAGAAUUCACGAACAUUUAGAGGAGGCCUCCCCUGGCUGUGUUUGUGCCCCACUUAGGAAGCGAUGGUGGAUUUCUCUGGGCAAAUUGUCGCCUUUACAACGCCAGGGGGCGGAGGCGGGAGGGAGAGCGGCGAGGGUAAGGGCGGGGCAACUGCUGACGUUCCCGGUGACGACUCCGGCUCAGCCCUCACCCUGGUUUCCGGCGGCGCGCGGCUCCCUUUUCCGCUCUCCCGCGCGCUCACAGGUACCGCCUCACUCCCACGCGCCCCCCAGCGCUGCGGUGCUAGACAGCUGAGAGAACAGACACAGACCUGUCGGAAGGUCCUCUGCAGGUCCCCCUUCCGCUCUGCCGAUCGACUUCCGCCUCGGGCAGUCAACAUACUGCCAAGGAAAUCUGAUGUGGAAAGGAAAAUAGAAAUAGUGCAGUUUGCUAGCCGGACACGCCAACUCUUCGUUCGAUUAUUAGCUUUAGUGAAAUGGGCUAAUAAUGCUGGCAAAGUGGAAAAAUGUGCGAUGAUUUCAAGCUUUUUAGAUCAGCAAGCCAUCCUGUUUGUGGACACUGCUGAUCGCCUGGCCUCGUUAGCUAGAGAUGCUCUGGUCCAUGCACGCCUGCCUAGUUUUGCCAUCCCAUAUGCCAUUGAUGUACUAACUACUGGAUCUUACCCACGGCUGCCAACCUGCAUUAGGGACAAAAUUAUUCCUCCAGACCCAAUUACCAAAAUUGAAAAACAAGCCACACUCCAUCAGCUGAAUCAGAUUCUUAGACAUCGGCUUGUAACCACAGAUCUUCCUCCUCAGUUAGCAAAUCUUACAGUUGCAAAUGGCCGGGUGAAGUUUCGUGUUGAAGGAGAAUUUGAAGCCACCUUGACUGUGAUGGGAGAUGACCCUGAUGUUCCAUGGCGUCUUCUCAAGCUAGAAAUUCUAGUUGAGGAUAAGGAAACAGGAGAUGGGCGAGCUUUGGUUCAUAGCAUGCAAAUCAGCUUCAUCCAUCAACUGGUGCAGUCUAGGCUCUUUGCUGAUGAGAAACCUCUUCAGGAUAUGUACAACUGCCUACAUUCUUUCUGUUUAUCACUUCAGUUAGAAGUGUUACAUUCCCAAACUCUAAUGUUAAUCCGAGAACGGUGGGGAGACCUUGUGCAGGUGGAAAGGUAUCAUGCUGGAAAGUGCCUCUCCCUUUCAGUUUGGAAUCAACAGGUUCUUGGGAGAAAAACUGGAACAGCAUCUGUUCACAAAGUUACAAUUAAAAUUGAUGAGAAUGAUGUCUCCAAGCCUUUACAGAUUUUUCACGAUCCUCCUUUGCCAGCUUCUGAUUCCAAAUUAGUAGAAAGAGCCAUGAAGAUCGACCACUUAUCAAUAGAAAAACUCCUGAUUGACAGUGUCCAUGCAAGAGCUCAUCAGAAGCUCCAAGAACUGAAGGCCAUUCUUAGAGGCUUCAAUGCCAAUGAAAACUCUUCCAUAGAGACUGCACUCCCAGCUCUUGUUGUUCCCAUCUUGGAGCCCUGUGGUAAUUCAGAGUGUCUGCACAUUUUUGUAGAUUUACAUUCUGGAAUGUUUCAAUUGAUGCUUUAUGGACUUGACCAGGCCACUCUGGAUGACAUGGAGAAGUCUGUGAAUGAUGAUAUGAAACGAAUCAUACCCUGGAUUCAGCAACUUAAGUUUUGGCUUGGACAACAGCGUUGCAAGCAGUCUAUAAAACAUCUGCCUACGAUAAGCAGUGAAACAUUGCAGCUUUCCAAUUACUCAACUCAUCCUAUUGGAAACCUUUCUAAGAAUAAACUGUUCAUUAAACUUACCCGCCUUCCACAAUACUACAUUGUUGUGGAGAUGUUGGAGGUUCCCAAUAAACCCACACAACUGUCGUACAAGUACUACUUUAUGUCUGUGAAUGCUGCAGAUCGUGAAGACAGCCCUGCAAUGGCAUUGCUGCUGCAGCAGUUCAAGGAAAACAUUCAGGACUUGGUUUUUCGUACAAAAACCGGGAAACAGACCAGAACCAAUGCCAAGCGCAAGUUGUCUGAUGAUCCAUGUCCAGUAGAAUCCAAGAAAACAAAACGAGCAGGAGAAAUGUGUGCCUUCAAUAAAGUUUUAGCCCACUUCGUCGCUAUGUGUGAUACAAAUAUGCCAUUUGUAGGACUUCGGUUGGAGUUGUCCAAUCUGGAGAUUCCACAUCAAGGAGUGCAAGUGGAAGGUGAUGGCUUCAGCCAUGCAAUUCGCUUAUUAAAAAUUCCUCCCUGUAAGGGUAUAACUGAGGAAACCCAAAAGGCUCUGGACCGCUCUCUUCUUGAUUGCACUUUCCGAUUACAAGGUAGAAAUAACCGCACUUGGGUAGCAGAGUUAGUGUUUGCAAAUUGUCCACUUAAUGGCACUUCUACUAGGGAGCAAGGACCAUCCCGGCACGUUUACCUGACAUAUGAAAAUCUGUUGUCUGAGCCUGUUGGUGGUAGAAAGGUGGUUGAAAUGUUUCUUAAUGACUGGAAUAGCAUUGCACGAUUAUAUGAGUGUGUGUUGGAAUUUGCACGUUCUCUACCAGACAUACCUGCUCAUCUAAAUAUUUUCUCAGAAGUUCGUGUUUAUAAUUACCGAAAACUUAUCUUGUGUUAUGGAACCACCAAGGGAAGCUCAAUUAGUAUCCAAUGGAAUUCGAUCCAUCAAAAAUUCCACAUUUCUUUGGGAACUGUUGGCCCAAACUCAGGUUGCAGUAACUGUCACAAUACCAUUCUCCAUCAGCUUCAAGAAAUGUUCAACAAAACACCAAAUGUGGUUCAGUUAUUACAGGUACUGUUUGAUACUCAGGCUCCAUUAAAUGCCAUCAACAAACUCCCCACUGUGCCGAUGUUGGGCUUGACCCAGAGAACCAAUACUGCCUACCAGUGCUUCUCCAUUCUGCCACAGUCGUCCACCCACAUCAGACUGGCCUUCAGGAACAUGUAUUGCAUUGAUAUAUACUGCCGGAGUCGAGGUGUUGUGGCAAUACGGGAUGGUGCCUAUAGUCUUUUUGAUAACAGCAAACUAGUUGAAGGUUUCUAUCCUGCACCAGGACUAAAGACGUUCCUGAAUAUGUUUGUUGACAGCAAUCAGGAUGCUCGAAGAAGGUCUGUAAAUGAGGACGAUAAUCCCCCUUCUCCUAUAGGAGGAGAUAUGAUGGAUUCUUUAAUAUCGCAGCUCCAGCCACCACCCCAGCAACAGCCAUUUCCAAAGCAGCCAGGAACAUCAGGUGCUUAUCCUCUUACUUCACCCCCUACAUCUUAUCAUAGCACAGUCAAUCAGUCUCCCUCAAUGAUGCACACACAGUCUCCAGGAAAUCUGCAUGCUGCCAGCUCCCCCAGUGGGGCUUUGAGAGCCCCAUCACCAGCGUCAUUUGUUCCAACUCCUCCCCCAUCCUCGCAUGGAAUCUCAAUAGGACCAGGGGCCAGUUUUGCUAGUCCACAUGGAACUCUUGACCCUAGUUCCCCAUACACUAUGGUGUCACCAAGUGGACGAGCAGGGAACUGGCCAGGAUCUCCUCAAGUGUCUGGCCCCUCACCAGCAGCACGCAUGCCUGGAAUGUCACCAGCCAACCCCUCACUACAUUCUCCGGUUCCAGAUGCUUCUCAUUCCCCUCGAGCUGGAACAAGUUCUCAAACAAUGCCAACAAACAUGCCUCCACCUCGUAAACUACCUCAGCGCUCUUGGGCGGCAUCCAUACCUACCAUCCUCACUCACAGUGCCUUGAACAUUUUACUGCUGCCCUCUCCAACUCCAGGCCUUGUGCCCGGCCUGGCAGGUAGUUACCUUUGUUCUCCACUUGAGAGAUUCCUUGGAUCAGUCAUCAUGAGACGACAUCUUCAAAGAAUUAUUCAACAAGAAACGCUGCAGCUGAUAAAUUCUAAUGAACCCGGAGUGAUCAUGUUUAAGACUGAUGCACUGAAAUGCAGAGUAGCUCUUAGUCCCAAAACCAACCAAACGCUUCAGCUAAAAGUGACACCUGAAAAUGCAGGACAGUGGAAACCUGAUGAACUUCAAGUUUUGGAGAAAUUCUUUGAAACAAGAGUUGCAGGACCACCAUUUAAAGCUAAUACGUUAAUAGCCUUCACCAAGCUAUUAGGAGCUCCUACACACAUCCUCAGGGAUUGUGUGCACAUUAUGAAGCUGGAGCUGUUCCCUGACCAAGCAACACAGCUAAAAUGGAAUGUUCAGUUUUGCCUGACGAUCCCUCCCAGCGCGCCGCCGAUUGCACCUCCUGGGACGCCUGCUGUGGUGCUGAAAUCCAAAAUGCUAUUUUUUCUUCAACUAACUCAGAAAACAUCGGUCCCUCCCCAAGAACCUGUUAGUAUUAUAGUUCCAAUCAUUUAUGACAUGGCUUCAGGUACAACCCAGCAGGCAGACAUUCCCAGACAGCAGAACUCUUCUGUUGCUGCUCCCAUGAUGGUCAGCAACAUUCUGAAGAGGUUUGCAGAGAUGAAUCCACCACGACAAGGUGAAUGCACAAUAUUUGCAGCUGUUCGUGAUUUAAUGGCUAAUCUUACACUGCCCCCUGGUGGGCGUCCAUAGACACUAUUGUUUUUAAACCAGGAAGGCUGACAGAUGAGACAACAAAAAAAAUCUGAAUUCAGCCUUCAGUUUAAAAAAGGAAAAGGACUUUUUUUUUAAACUUUAAGAGCUAAAUAUUCUAAACUGGCAAAAAUUUUCAGGGUGCACUUCUUUCAUCAAAAUGAUCAUCCAUCUUUUGUAUAAUGAACUUGUAUAGUGUGUUUAAAUGGGACACAUUUCAAAGGAAAUAAAUCAGUGUCCGUUUGCCAGUAAUAAAUUUAAUAUUCUGUUUUAUACUAUAAAGUUAUGAAAAUGCCAAACUUGUUUAUUUAAUUGUUUUCUUAUGUUUUGGGUGUAAUAGUCCUUUUUUGGUUUUUGUUUUGUUUUUUAAGGCAGGUCUGUCAUUUUUGAAUACUGUAAAACUGUGAUAAACUUUAUAUUGAAGCUGUAUUUUAAUAUGACCGCUUUGAAUCCUUACAUGAAAUGUUCUGGGAGUUGUUAUAAACACACCCCAAGGAAGCAAUAUUUAAUAAAACUAGGUCAAAAACAAAACAAAACAGUGACACUCACUUGUGUGUAUAUAAACUCUAGAGACAUCUUAGGCCCUCCCUUCAUCUUUAACCUGGUGGAUGGAGCCAGUUAUUAAUUUAUAAUAAUACAUGUCUGAAAUUUGACCAAAAACAUCUUCUUUAUGUCAAGGUUAAUAUAUUUUCUUCAGACAUUCCUAACUUGACUAGUGGUUAACAUUUAGCACCUUGGUUGUCUUUCAAUAUAUAGGAUUUGGGUGAAAAAUAAGGAACUUAGUCUUUGAGAAGGGACAGUAUGUGGUUCGUAUUGAUCAAGGAUCCCAAAUAAUGCAAUCAUUCUCAUCUGUUGAGGAUGUGGGAACUUUUCUGUCAGGAAAAUUUAGUUUACAGAAUACUUCUGCAUACAACAUUAAUUAGGAAACAAAGAACUUUAAUGCUGUACCUCUGCAUGAAGUUUCUGUGAGCUUUCUUUAUCUUGCUUAACUUAUCCUCCUUUCCUUCCCCACCAAAAUUGGGAUUGUUCUAAACAAUUUCAAUUUAAUUCAUUGUCAACAAAACGAUAGAAUGUUUUGCUUGGAAGAAACCUGGUCCAUUCCCCUCAUUGUGAAGAAUCCCGAAUCCUGGGCCUGUCCAGGGUCAAAUGGAGUUUUUGGUAUUAAUACAUCUCUGCAGGGUUUCUUUUUGGAGCACUGUGCUGUCUUUCCUAGUCAGUCAGGGACUUUUUUAAGCUUCAAAGAACAUGGUCUGAUGCAAAGGUCUUCUACCGACUUCAUGGUAUUUAGGAAAAAUUUUUAAGUGAUAAUACCAUGCCGAGUUACCUGGUCACUGUAAUACUGGUUCUCCAUUAAAAUGUAGAUGCUUUGUCUAAUUCCACUUCAAGAUGAUUUAAUUGAGCUUCUAUAACUAUCAACUAUCAAAUUCUAGUUUCAAGUAUCUCACUGUACCUAUAUCAUAUCUGUUCUCAACUUUGUUUGAUUCUCCACUCAUUUUCAAUCAGAGUUGAAGCCUUCUUUGCCUUUCUUCUUUGUCUUAUUUCUGCCUUCAUCUCCCACUUCUCACCCAACUCUGCCACUGUUCAGGAGCAGUUGACUAAACUUUUAUCCUUCCUUUAACUUAAUCUUUUUAUCCUUCUGUUUUUAGUUCUUACAGUGGUAAUCACAUCAGUUUGGCAAUCUAAGAUGUCUUUAUCAAGGGUCAGCCCUUUUCUAUUUGGAGCUGAAUCUUUUCUUUCAUGUAGAAAUCUACAUGUAUAUACAAGAAAUGUAUUUUUAUCUGCAGGAUAAUAUUGUUUCAAAUAAUUUUAUUAAGAGUUAACUUUUUAGGUAUUUUCCCUUUUAAUGUGGUUUUGAAAUGUUAAUUGCAUUUUUACACAUGAUGCAUUCAGUGGACACUCUUUUUUCCUAAUUAUAACUCAUCUCUGAAUGCAUUGUGCCAAUCAAGAGUAAGAUAGGAUUCAGUGCGCAAAAUUUGCUUUUGAUGCUUAUUAAGAGUAAACCCAUGAAUUUGAAUUUUUAUAUUAUGCUUGGUACUUGGAAUUGAUAUAUACCUUAUUAAAGCUUGAAAACAUUUAGCAUUUGAAUAGUAAGUUUCAUCACAAAUCAUGUCUUUUGCCUCUUUUGUUACCCAGGUUCGAUCAAGGGGACUGGAUGCCCAAGUGAUUUUCUCUAAUAAUCGGGUUGGGACUUAACUUUAAGGUGUUUUCAAUGUGAUUUUAGUAUUUACAGUAAUAAAUAAAAUUUAUACAAAGUUUCAGAGAACUACCAACUCUCUAGUUAAUUUUGAUGAAGAUGUUUUCAUUAAUAGUCUGGUUUAGUAUUAAUUUAACCUUGAAAUAAGAAAUUGGUCCUGAUUUGCCACCUUCAUUUUUCCAUCUGCUGAAAUGCCAUUUCAGAAUGUAUAAAAGUACUUUCAGAAUUAGAAGAAAAGUGAGAGCUUCAGCAGAACGUGUCAAGUCGCUAAUAACAGGAGUCGAACCUUAUGUUUGAAAAUUAACUGAGUGAGUUAAGUGCAAGCAUAAACUAAAAUUUAUAUGACUUUGAAUUUAAGAACCACUAAUAACUGUGUUCUAAUUAACACAGUAAUCUGUUCAGCCAAAGGAUACUAACAGCCAUUCUUUGGACUGUGGUUAAUUUGAUAACUUCAAGAAGUUAUAACUUUGCUACCCUGGAUUCUGAUGCAAUUUCAAUAUAAAAAGUUGUUCCUUUCAUAGUUUUUCCCCCCAAAAGAAGUGCCUAUUACAUUUUACCUUAAUGUUUAUUUAUCAUCCAAGUGUUCUUGAUAUAAAAUCAGUAUACAGAAAAUUUUAAGAGAACUUACAUUCAAGGGACAUAGAGGGAAAAUGUUAAUGUGUAUUUCAUUGUUUCUUGUGGAAUUUUUUUUUCAUUCGGUUUGAGAAUGGACAGUGUGUCUAAGGAUGUGAUUUAAAUUUACUUAGGAUGGAUUUAGCAUUGAGGUUAUUAAGACAAAGUUAGCAGAGGCCAGCCAGCACUGUGCUGCACAACUCCAGGAACUCCAUGGUAUGCUCACAAUUUUCUGCAAGUUGCCUCCACUUCCAAGUGGCCAGUGAUUUGUUAAAAUACCUUGCCCAAGAAUAUAACUGAUUGAUGAAAGGGCAUAUUUAGGUCAAUAUAAAAUAAUAGCAAGUAUUUACUGAGAGCUUACUGUGUGCUAGGCAUUUUCUUAAUAUUUCAAUGUGUAUUUAAUCCUCACAACAACCCAAUGUGGUAGGUUAUUGAUAUCCUCUUCUUAAAAAUGAGUAAAUGGAGGCCCAGAGAAAUGUAAUUUGCCUGAGAUCAAAUUAAGGUUGCUUAAGAUCAAACUGCUAAGAAGGGGCAGUUUGAGUCUGAGCUAGUGCUCCUAAACACUGGACAUUUUUGCUGUGAACCACAGUCGGGAAGGUUUAAUGUUUAGACUCUUUCCUCAGAGGCUUUUAACUACACACAAUUUUGACAUGUUUUCCAAGCUCAGAAAGCUCAUUAAAAACAACUAAAACUGA